AGUGUGAUUCGACUUGUCCCUGAGGAGUACAGAGAACACUCUUCCUGUUCCUCUGCAGCUGAAGGAUGAUGGCUGAGCCCUGGCAGGCCCUACAGCUCCUGUUGGCCAUUCUAUUGACUCUGAUGGCCCUCCCCUACCAAGCAAGGAAGAAAACCUUUCUAAGCGUCCAUGAAGUGAUGGCAGUAGAAAACUAUGCGAAGGACAGCUUGCAGUGGAUCACCGACCAGUAUAACAAGGAAAGUGAUGACAAGUACCACUUCAGGAUCUUCCGAGUCCUUAAAGUCCAGAGGCAGGUCACUGACCACCUGGAGUAUCACCUGAAUGUGGAAAUGCAGUGGACCACCUGCCAAAAGCCAGAGACCACGAACUGUGUCCCCCAGGAAAGGGAGCUUCACAAGCAAGUCAACUGCUUCUUCUCAGUGUUUGCUGUACCCUGGUUUGAACAGUACAAAAUUUUGAACAAAAGCUGCAGCAGUGACUAGGUGUCCUGGAGUGUACAACUGCGGCCACUGCAUGUGAGAGAAUCCUGCAAUGGGCAAUAAUCCUUAAUAUAGGCAAUAAAUGUUUGUCAACAUA